AGAGUGACGGCGACAGGCGCUGGCGGAGGCGGCAGCCUCCUAGCACCUCUUACAGCUGCCGCCGCAGACGCCAACCCGGGCGGAGGGGGCGCAGGCGUUAGUAGUGCCCACCACCACGUUGCUGUUGCUGGGGACGCUACUGACUCUGGUGGAGACAACAGGGGCAGUAGUGGAGGCGCAGAGAUCGCCACAGACAACGCCACCGCGGGAGCUGCUGACGCCUGCAGGGGAAAGAGACGGAGGCGCGCGUCAGGCGCAGCCGCGACCUGGGUGAGUGGCUUUGCUGCGAGCCCACGCGCCCUUUGCCCAGAGGCUCCCAGACCCGCCCAGCGGGAGGAGGGGACGGACCCCACUACUUACAGACAUUCACCGAGCCGACGCCCUCGCACAGCCUGCAGGGAGAGAAGGCGAGAGGUCAGUGCCGCGGAAAAGGCGCCGGGCCCCCGUGACUGAAGUGGAGGGGGACAUCUGUGGCCCUCCAUCUGGGCACUUGCCCAAGGGAAGGGGCAAGAAAUGCUCUCGGCCAGGAGCCAGUGUAGACUCGGGUCACCGUGAGGGUCUGGAGACAGAAGGCCUGUGAGUGCCUCGCUCUCCACUGCUUCUGAGCUGUGCAACCCCAGCUUGGGCCAACCUCAGCCUAGGCUUCCUCAUCAGGAAAACCUACUUCGUAGAUCUCUUGCGAGGACUGAAUCAAAUAAGAAGCGUCCAGUGCUUAGUGCCUGGCUCAUAGCCCUUAAGAGCUAUUAGCUGCCACUACCUCGAAGUUGGUUCUGACUGAAUUGCAGGUGCAUUUGAGGGGAGCAGAUUUAACUUCUGAAAUCCAGUCUGAUUGGUGUCAUUAGAUUAUAGGCAUCAGGAGGGUAGACAUUUUUGUCUAUUCCUUCCUGCACCACCUAAAAACAAUGCCUGGCUCAAUACAAAACUGUUAGAUAAACAAAUGGGAUUUUAGAACAGGCUCAGAGACUGCCCACCACAGUCCUCUCAUCCGGCAGAUGGAAAGGCUGAGGCCCAGAAGGAGGACAUAUCCAAUGACAAGGCAGGGCUGUCACCCCAGACACUCAUUUCUACCCACCCCACAUUUCCCUCCCAAUAGCUUCCCCUAAGGGAAGAAAAUGGAGUUCCCCUGAAAGCACACUGGCCAAGGAUUGGUUAAAUCAGCUUCAGAUAAGAGAAGCCAUGGCCACCAUCAAAUCAUUCCAUGCCCAGGUUCCCUAGGUAACACAUACCAAAGCUCCUGAGUUCACUCCAAGAGCCCCGUGUGAUGGAGGAGUGGGCCACUCAGAUUCCAAUGCCAUCUCCAUGUGUUUCUCCAACUUCCAAAUUCAGACUUGGAAAACUCCUCCUCCCAGAAUUCUUCACUUAUGAAAUUCCCCAGGCCCAGCCAGACAGACCCCUGCCUCUGAGCUUUCCAAUGGAACAACUCGAGUUUGGUGGAAAUCUCGUCAUAUGGUCACUUUAGUUUCUAGGUCCCAAACCUGUGUUCCCCAUUUCCCAAAUAAACAAGAUGCUCCCUCUGCAUCCCCAACCUUCACCCUCCUCUCCCCAGGGCCAAGGGCCUGACUGUCCACAAAAAAAAAGGAGCUUCGAGUGAGACCAACUGACCAACUAGGGGAAAGAAACCAAGGGCAAAGAAUGAGCUCACAUUCUGGGAGUGUUGUCCUUCUGGGAGCAGGAGCUGUAUAGCUGCCCUCCAGCUGUAUCGCUGGCCUCCAGCCAUAGGAAGGCUGAGUGACCAAUGGGUCUUCUCCACUCCCCCCACCUCUGAAGCAAGCAAACAAGCAAAAAUCCUGAAAGCAAGGCAUAACUGCCCCAAGGGAUAAGUCCUUGCUCUCUGCCUAACUCAUUCCCACCUGCCACAAUGGAAUACCACUUUGGGAUGCUCAUUGGCACUAUAAUAGAAAAGCAUGAGUUGAUAGUGUCAUCUAUCUGAAGCUGUCCUUAUGGGAUACAUCUGAACUCCCAGGUCUAGAUGGGGCCAGGGCCAGACUAGGAAAAAGAGAAGGAAUCCUGAGAAGCACAUGCAGCUACAGCUGGAAGGGAAGAAGCACUACCCAGGCAAGCUGACCCCAAGCCUUAAUUAGGCUUCUCAGUAACAGGAAUACCUGCUGCCAGAUUACUGGAUCUCAACUGAGAUGAACAAGACUGCAAUCUCAGAUCAGUGCCUGGGUGAACAUGAGAGACUCAAACGGGGCUAGAUCAUACUUAAAGGACUUACACAAAUUACCUGUCUGGUUGCAGGGUGGGGAGGUUAAGAAACAAAACUUAAAUGCUGCCAGGAGUGUGAGGACAGAGCACACUGAGAACCCUGGCAGGGCUGGGAAAGGGAAAGGUCUAUGGGACCCACCUCUGCUCCUCGCCCUCCAGCAGGCGCCUGUAGGUGGCGAUCUCGAUGUCCAGGCCCAGCUUGGAGUUCAUCACCUCCUGGUACUCCCUGAUCAGGCAGGCCAUGUCCUGCUUGGCCUUCUGCAGGGCACCCUCCAGCUCGGCCAACUUGCAGCGGGCAUCGCUGAGGGCCGCCUCACCCUGCUGCUCAGACUGAGCCACCGCAGCCUCCAGCUUGGAAUUCUGAAGAGAACAGAGAGAACAAGGUAGAUUAGAGUCCCUGGGUCUCUCUGAUGCUUACCUCGAUGAGACCAUGCUCCCCACCAAGCUGGGAGCACCCCAGAACAGAGCCUCUUGCCUUCAUCACCUGGGACUCACAGAGACCACAACCAGGGACUCUACAUGGACAGAGGGGCUGGAGAAUGAAUGCUGAGAUCCAGAUAGGGCACACAUAGGCUGUGUGACCAUGGUUAGACCCUCGGUCUCUCUGACCUUGGGCACAGAUGCCCCAUACCUGGCACUUGGCAUUCUCCACCUCAGCCGUCAGCCUCUGGAUCAUGCGGUUCAGCUCGUUGAUCUCCUCCUUGGUGCGGCGCAGGGUCUCCCCGUGCCUGAUCACCGUGGCCUUCAUCUCCUCACACUGGGGGAAGUAGAGAUGCUCAUGAGGUUCAGGGUGGGACCUCCCACCCAUUCAGGGCAUGACAGAUGAUUUUGCAGGUUGUGCAGUGCUCAGCCUGUGCAACCACACAUGGCAGUCCUGCCCUACCACCCCAACAUCAGAGUGGCAGCCAUCUCUUCUCAUCCCUAGUGCAUCCCCAGAAAAGGAAGCCUAUUUAAUAGAUAAUCUCAAAUCCCUCCCACUGCCAUGUCUAGCAGGCAGGUGUCCUGUGCCACUCACCUUGCUGCGGUACCAGGACUCGGCCUCAGCCCGGCUACGGGUGACAAUGUCAUCGUACUGUGCCUUGAUCUCGGCAAUGAUGCAGUCCAUGUUCAGGUCCCGGCUGUUGUCCAGCUUGACAACCACGGAGGUGUCUGAGAUGUGGGACUGGAGAACGCGGAUCUCCUGCAGGAGGUGAGGGCAGUGACUUUAGUUGAGAACACAGCCCCACCCACCAUGUCCUGACUCCACCUCCUCAGGCUUUCUCUGGUCCCCAACCCUGCCCCCUCACACAGCCUCAGGGACUGCAACCUCUACCCACAUCCUGUCCAACACUCCCACCCCCAUCUCUCCUCUCUGCUGGCUGCCAGGUCUCUGCCUGGCCCCUGAGCCCGCACCUCCUCAUACAGCCGCCUCAGGAAGUCGAUCUCCUGGAUCAGGGCCUCCACAUUGGCCUCCAGGUCUGAUUUGCGGAGGUAGGCGCAGUCCACAUCCUGGAAAGGUGGGGAGUGUUGGAGCUCAAGGACCCUGGUGAUCCAGCCUCUAGAUUCCUCUCUCUUCCCACCCAUUCCAUGAAGCCUGGGGAAAGGAGUCCCCAGUGUCUCAUUCCCAUGCCCUCUCCUUCCCUUCUGGCCCUUCCCGGGGUGACCUGGCAUCCUCUGCCAUUCUGAGGACAAACCCUGUUUGUCUUGGGCACGGCUCACCAGCCUUUCACUGCUCCUUACCCUCUUAUCUCUCCUUUCUCCCCUCUCCUGCUCCAGGAAGCCUGCCCAGACUGACCCCCCAGCUCUCACACCCUGACCCUUUCCUGUCCCCCAGCAGUGCUCCAAAAGCCCAAGGGCUACUCCUGGUUCUUCUCCAUCCCCCCUUAGAACCUGGGAUUGUGUCUCUGCCUCAAGGUCAGACUCCCCAAAAUGCUAGACAGACUGCACUGUCUCUCAGCAGAGACAUUGUAUCUGCUAUGGCUCCAGGGGCCUCAGCAAUAGACCACAACCUCUGGAACAGAGCAGGACACACAGAGGACAGUGCAGCCAUCCCCUUGCCCAAGGUAGGUGCUGGUAGAUAUUCCCAAGUCAUUGCCCUUUGUCAAGGCCCUGGAUGCUCAAUACAAAGGCCUGCAUCUGGGCAGUCCUAGCCUGCUGUGGAAAGGUCAUUGUGCCCCACGCUGAGGUUGAGACCCCCUGUGUGUCCCCAGGAAGAAUCUGUCAUUCUGAGAUCCCACAGAUCUGUGCUUCUCAAUCCUGUGUCACUUGCCUUCUUCAGAGCCACAAACUCGUUCUCAGCUGUUGCUCUCAGAGAAACCUCCUCCUCAUACCUGAGACAGAGCAGAGGGAAGAGAGGGGAGGUCAGGGCAGGGCAGGUCUCUGCAGAGCCACCAUCACAUCACACUUCAUCACAGCCAUGGGGACAGUACUAGAAACACCUCCACACAGCCCCGGCCUGGCAGCCUAGCUUAGUGCUUUCUAGUUGGAUGUGGGAUGUGUCUGGGAUUCUCUAUCCACUUUGAACUGGGGAUGGAGAGUGCUCAUCUGGGACCUCCCAGUCCUGUUCCCAAAGGGGCUCUGAGGUCCCCCAGGAGGCAAAUAGGACUCAGCCCCCAGCCCCAUCCUGGGAGUGGACAGCGUGGACUCUCAGGGCCUGUAGCCCUAGCCUCCCCUCACUGGUAUCAAUCCCAGCUCAGGUAUGGGGCCUCCUGGACCCGCAGACCCUCAGGACUUAGAACCUAAGGCAGUGCGACACCCAGAGCCCAAGACCUGUCACUCAUGAGAGACCCUGGGCUCACAUCUGACAGGUGCUACAAGUAUAGGGGCUGAGGGUCAGGAGAGAAGGCCUGGACCCUGCAGAGGCUUCCUCCCCACCCAGCGCAGGGGAGAGCUGCUGGGUGAUGUGGUUCAGGGAGAGAAGGCUGAAGUGGGACAGAGACAGGUCAUGGGAGUCACAGCCCUCCUCUUACACAGGUGUCUGGGCAAAGAUUCCACAAAGGAAAAGACCCCGCCACCCUCGGUCAAUCUAGUGGUCAUGGCCACUCACCCUACCUGGGAGUUCUUAUUGUCUAAUCCAGUGUAUUUAACCUAAACCCCAUUCCUGUGCCCAGCAUCCCUCUUGCCCGCACUCACUUCUUCUUGUAGCCCUCCAGCACCUCCUGCACGUGGUUAAGCUCUGAGGCCAGCCUCCCGCUGUCGGCCUCCACGCACUCGGCCUCCCGCCGCAGAGUCUCGAUGUAGCCCUCAAACAGGGGCUCCAGGUUGCUCUGGCAACACUCGCGGUUCUGGUAGAACUGCAGCUUUGUCUCCAGCAGUUUGUUCUGCUGCUCCAGGAAGCGCACCUGCCAUUCGGUGUGGGAAGGUGGGGCAGAUGGUGUCUGGUGCCCCAAAGCCAGCUCUGGGGGCUCGCAGGGGAGGUGCUUUAAUGGGAACCCCCAAAUCUGGAGCUUAUCUGAGAUUGAGUAGAGGUGGGCAGUGGGAGACAGACAAUUUCUGGAUUUCCUGGUCAUGAUCUGUGUCUAGAUUUCCCACUCAGGAGUGGAGCAAGGGCUGGGUGGUGUCAGUGCCUGCUCCCUGGGGAGUUGAGUGACCCCCCCCCCACCCCCCACCCAAGCAGAUGAACAGAAGUAGAGGCUCAGUCCCUCACUAUGAAACUAGGUGAUCAGCAACCCACACAGGCAGAGUACUCAGGUUCAGAUCACAGAUGAGGUUUCUGGGGAUGGUGCCAGGAAGAGGGUGUCACAGGCCAUCUGGAAGGGAGCUCAGCUGUCCCAGCCCUUCCCCUGUGUCAUCUGGAAGUCAGUGCACCCUACUCUCUCACCCUGGGGCUGCCCAAACCCCUCUGAGUUCAGCAGCAGUGGUCACAUGCCCCCCUCCCCCAACUCCCUGAUGUCUAGCUUGUGCCCCAGAGCAGCCUGGCCACACUUUUCCUUCACAAGCUCCCUCUAUCUGAACUGUCAGCUGAGUCUGCAUCUUGAGUGCCUGUGUGUGUGUGUCUGUGCAUGUGUCUGUCUGUCUGUGUGUCUGUGUGCCUCGCCCAUCAGACUGGGAUCUCAGGCAGGCAGAGGUCUUUGUGCCUCUGACUCCAUCCUUAGUGCCCGGCCCUGGCUGUGUAGGUGGUGGGGGUUCAGGAAGGGUGUGAUCCAGGACACCCACCUUGUCGAUGAAGGCCGCGAACCUGCUGUUGAGGGACUUGAUCUGCUCCUUCUCCUCCUGCUUCACGCACUGCGCGUUGGGGUCGAUCUCCAGGUUGAGGGGCGUGAGGAGGCUCUCGUUGACCGACACGGUGGUGAUGCAUGGGGGACUGGGCCCGCACACGCCCCCGGAGCGGUAGCCGAAGCUGCGUCCGCAGGAGCCGGCCCGAAAGCCUCCGCACACGCUGUGGCUGCCGAAGCCCCCGGUGAGGCCGCGGUAGCAGGAGAUGCCACGGUAGGGGGCGGCGGUGAUGCAGCAGCGGCCGGGCCGGGGCCCGCAGGCCGAGAUGCAGCUGAAGGCGCGGCCACCACAGACCAACUCACGUCCCGCACACCCACCUCAACCUCCCAAUACACAGUUGAGGAAACUGACGUUGGACGAAGGAGUGGGCAGUGACUCAGGUUGGAAUGGAAGGGAAGGGGCGGGGCUGCUGCUCUUUCUGUCCUGCGGGGUUUGACAUGGUCAAUGCCGCUGUCCGCGGUGCUCAUAGGACUAGCCAGGAAUGUUGGGAGGGGGAAUCCCUUGAUGUGGAACUUGGGGGGCGCUUGGUGGUUUCUCCGAACUAGAUGACCUGUUUCUGCACCCCAAAAGACCCACGUUUACAGAAUCUCUAACUUAGUCACCUUCUCAGGGACCCAGUUCCUCCACACCUACUCCCAAAUCCCUUAUCUAUACCUAUCAACAUGUUUUUUUCUCUCUCUCUCUCCCACUCUCUGGUGCACACACACAUACACACACAAACUCACACACAAUGCACUCACAUGCUGGCCUUCCUACUCACAACCCCCCCUCUCUCUUUCACAUACACACUCACACACACAAUGCUUUCACAUGCUGGCCUUUCUACCCACCAUCUCACACACACACACACACUCACAGGUCCUCACCUGCACAUUCAACUAGCAUGUAGACUAGUCCUCAGGCCACCUUAUUAGGUCAUAUUGGCCAGCCUCGGCUGAGAGGAGGCAUUCCCUCCCUCAGAGUGUCCCAUGCGGCCUCAGGAGCACACACUAGCCCACUGGCCCCAGGAAAGCACAAUUACCUCCCACAAGGCCCUAGACAAGGAUUGAAUGUCUGGAUGUCCUCUCAGGCCUCUGUGUAACCUCCAGGGCCUAGAAGGUCUGGGAUGAGCACCACUGUUAUGCAUCUAUACAGUAUCUGGCUCAGAAUAUGAGAUCAAAUAGAGCCACAUGAGGAGAGCAUCCAGCCCCUGCCAUCAUCCCCUGAGUCCCUGCUGCUUUCUGCACUAUACUCCUUGAAACUCCUGCACAGAAGUUUGUCAGUACCCUUGGCAGGUGCCAGAGAACAGAUCUAUAUUUGUAUGUGCCAUCCAUCCAGUGUGAAUAGUGUGGGUCUUAAACUCACAAAGGCUGGGUAGGAACCAAGGCUCUGCCCUGAGUACCCCUGUGUGAUCUAGGGGAAGGCACUUGACUCUCCUGGGAAAUAGGUUAAGGCUUUCCCUCCUACUACUGCCUUAGAGUUACAGAAAUGUGUACAUGCUCAGUGGACUCCAGAGCACAGAGCAGAUGGGCUUCAUUACAAUCAUUAGGAAGCGGUGGGCUCAGGGGCAGUGUUUAUUCAGAAUUCAUGUUCUGACCCACUAAUUGAACCAACCAGAAUUUUAUUUUAAUGAAAUUGAUUAUGAGAAAAUCAAAUAGAGUAGAAUAGACCAGAAAAUAGCAGAUUGCACCUUAUGUCAUGGGAAUAACUUGUUACAUGCCCUUUUUGUUUCAGUUGUAUGGCCUAUGUAUAUGUAUGUGCAUACUCAGUCACCAUGUAAAAUUAUUUCUUAUUAUAGUUGCAGCAGAAAAGUUGAAAUAUCUAUUUCUCACUGUAUACAAAAACCAAAUUAAAAUGGAUUAAAGACUUAAAUAUAAGACCUCAGACUAUGAAACUACUAGAAGAAAACAUUGAGGAAAUGCUUAGGGCAUUGACCUGGACAAAGAUUUCUUGAUUGAGACCUCAAAACCAAAGGCAACCAAAGCAAAAAAUGGGCAAAUGGGAUCACAUCGAGCUAAAAGAACUUCUGCACACCAAAGGAAACAAUCAACAAGUUGAAGAAAUGACCUACAGAAUGGAAGAAAUAUUUGCAAACUAUUCAACUGACAAGGAAUUCGUAGCUGCAAUAUAUAAGGAACUCAAACAACUCAAUAGCAAGUAAACCAAAUAAUCUGAUUUUAAAAUGGGCAAAAGAUCUGAAUAGACAUUUCUCAAAAGAAGACAUAUACAUGACCAACAGGUAUAUUGAAAAUGCUCAACAUAUCAUCAAAGAAAUACAAAUCAAUACCACAAUAAGAUUAUCAUCUCAACCCAAUUAAAAUGACUUUUAUCAAAAAGACAAAAAAAUUAUGGAUGCUGGCAAGGAUGUGGAGAAAGGGGAACACUUGUACACUGCUAGUGGGAUGUAAGUUACUACAGCCACUAUGGAAAACAGUAUGGAGUGUCCUCCAAAAGCUAAAAAUAGAACCACCAGGUGAUCCAGCAAUCCCACUACUAGGUAUACAUCCAAAAGAAAGAAAAUUCUUAUAUCAAAGAGAUGUCUGCACUCCCACGUUUAUUGCAGCGCUAUUCACAAUAGCCAAGAUUUGGAAUCAAACUAAGUGUCCAUCAAUGGAUGAAUAAAGAAAGUAUGUUACAGAUACACAAUGGAAUAUUAUUCAGCCAUAAAAAGGAAUGAAAUCCUGUCAUUUGCAACAACAUGGAUGGAACUGGAGGACAUUAUGUUAGGGAAAAUAAUUGAGGUACAGAAAGACAAAUUUCAGAUGUUCUUACACAUAUGCGAGAGCUAAAAAAAUUGAUCUCAUCAGAUAGAGAGUAGAAUGAUGGUUACCAGAGGCUGGGAAGGGUAAUGGGGAGGGGAAGAUAAAGACGUGUUAAUGAGUACAAAAAUACAGUUAGAUAACAGAAAUGAGAUCUAGUGUUCAGUAGCACAAUAGAAUGACUAUAGUUAAUCAUUUAUUGUGUAUUUCAAAAUAACUAAAGGAGUAGGCUUGGAAUGAUCCCAACACAAAGAAAUAAUAAAUGUUUGAGGUGAUGGAUAUUCCAAGUACUCUGAUUUGAUCAGUACACAGUUUAUGCUUAUCUCAAAAUAUCUUAUGUAGCCCAUAAACAUGUAUAACUAUUAUGUACCCAUAAAAAGAAAACAUUAAAAUAAAUAAAUAAAUAAAUAAAAAGUUUGAAUACAUGGCAUAUUAGUUAAGCACACAGACUCAGAUUCCAAACUGCCUCGUUUCGAAUUCUAGCUCUGCCACUCUCUAGCUGUGUAAACUCAGGCAAUUACUUAGCCUCUAUGUACCUCAUUUCAUGAUUUCUAAAAUGAAGAUAAUAAUAGUACCCACCUCAUAAAGUUGUAAAGAUUAAAAGAGUUAAUCCAUGUAAAUCACUGAGAACUAAGCCUGGCACACUCUAAGUGUGUAAUCAUAUUAGUUGUUGUUGUUGUUGCUGCUGAUGCUGCUGCUGCAGACGUAUCAACAGCAUUGAUGGGAUAUACUCAUCCACAUGCCUAAGCCAUCUGUGUCCAGUUUUCAUUAACCGCCUUAUCUUAAAGAACUUGUAGAAGGAUUAAAUGAAAUAAUGCAUGGACAAUGUUUAACAGCAGCUGGCACAUAGAAAAUGCUCAAUAAAUGUUAUCUACUAUAUUCUACAGUGGGAGCCAGUCCAAGGGGCAGAGGAUCUGAGAAGUUUGGCCAUGGUUACUCCAUUUGUCCUCGAAAAGAACCCCAAAACACAUGCCCCUCCUUCAAUCUCUGCUCCAGCCUGAUUGCCUCAGAGAAGGUCCAAAGAGAAUCUCUUCUCUUUGGCAAAGGAACACACCACCAAUCCUUGGGUAACCAUACUACUGGAUGAGAAGAGAGGCUUGGAUAAUCUAAAAAUUCUGUAAUCUGUGAAUAAUUCAUAAGUGUGUAUUUAUUAUUUGGACUUAACAGACCAUCAGAAAUCCUCAGUCAUAAAUUAAAUGAUGGCACACUCACUCAUCUUUAUUUUUGCCUGAUCCUAAAACCUCCUGAUUGGUCAGUAGCCAGAGGAUUUCAUGAGGUUGAGGAUGGGGGAUAUGGACUUGAUAAUUCAUCCAAGUAUAAUGGUGCUCCAAUGAGAGCAAGAGAAGGCAAGCUUUCAUUGCAGAUGGACAAAUGGAAGUUGGAGUUGAGGAAGAACUUGCCAGAAGACAAGUAGUCAUUACUUUCUAAAGGAGCUUGCAUUAUCUCUUCCAUUUAGGGAGGCUUUAAGUAAAAGAAAGACACUUCUUAUUCUGCAGUGGCCACCAUUUUUGUGGAGACAAGGUGAACCAAAAGACCUUCAGAUCUGGAGAUCAGAAUCUCUUCUUUUAGCCCAAGUGGACCUUUAUUUCAAGGGGCACUUGUAAAGAAUGGGCAAAUUAGGUGGUUUUAACAUUAGAAAGUUCUUGUUCAGUGCUCCCUUCGGUUCAUUCUGCUCCCUGGAGGGUAUUAUAAGGCAGACUCCUCAAGAUAGUUGAUCGCUUAGACUAGACAACAUUUUCCAGAUGGGGGACUCGGGGAUUUUGUGACUGAUAUUUCCUAGCUCUAUGCUCAAUCCUGUCUUAAUUUUGGAGGGAAGGAGGCAUUAAGAGGAGGAAGGAAACAUGGGUUCUGGAGCUCCCAGUCUGGUAGAGCAUAUCCAAAUUCAUGAGAAAGGCCAGAAGUCUAAAGAGGGCUACUUUUCAUACAUACUGUCAGAUACUGAGGCAUGCAAUGACUGCUGACAGUGUCCUUUCUGGGACAAUGUGCAAUUGCAGCUAGUCUGAUGGGAAAGGCAAGAAAGGCUCCCUGGAAAGGGUGAGGACAAGCUUUAGGCAAAAGGCGGGCAGGACAGUGUUGAUGAGAAGAUGUGCAUGGAAGCAUUUCACACAGUGACAGACAAUGAGACAGGGCUAGUGGGUGGACAACAGGUGAUCCUGUGGGCCCUUGCAGGAGUGGAGAGGAUCAUGAGAUACUGUGACAGCGGAGAGAGAGGGAGAAUGCCGGUUGAGGCACAGCCCUCAUAAGCAGGGACAGUGUCGUCCCUGAGACUCUGCUACACAGCUGUGGGCUGGAAGGCAGCCUGUAGGCUCUACAUCUGGAGCAUCUGCAUGCUGGGCUUACAGGUCUCCAGAGGGCCAUGCCCUUACUAACCUUGCAGCUGGCUCAUGCUUUCUACUCAUAGAAAGCAGGUGCAGGCCAGGGUCCAGUGAAGGAAGUUGAGAGGUAGUGGAGUGGCUGCUUACACAACACCUGGGAUGUUGAGAUGUUGAUAAUGGAAUUGACCUCAGGCCAGUUGGGUGGGUGAUUGGGGAGAGCCCAAGUCAGAGCCCUGCCUUCUCAGCCAAGAGAGCCCAGGACGCUGGCCAAUUAUCCAUCAGAACUCACCAGAGAGGAGUCCCACUGGACAAAGGGCCAGAAGGCCCCUGUAAGAUGCCUGGGUGGGGCUGGAGCCUGACUCAAAAGCUCCACCCUGGUAACAUUCAUCCCACUAACCAGCUGGGUGCCUGCACCUCCCUCGCCCCAUGUCCCUGCCCUGUGAGGGUUCAUUACUAUAAAUCUGGAACUACAGUGCCCACCUCUUCCAGUGGGCCUACACACACUUUCCCUUGGUGCUGUGCUGCUUCCCCCAUCCACCUCCUCCUCCUCUGCUCUUUCAUCCCUGGAGUGACCCUUCCACCAUACUUCCCAGAUCUUCUCCCAUUUUUCCUCCACUGUCCUCCAGUUUCCUCCUCUUCCUGACUAUCUCCUAAGAUCUCUCCCUCAUUUUCUUCUCCACCCAUGCAGCACUCUCCUUCUCUUCUUCUAAGUCACCCUGAGAAUAAUAGUCUAAGACCAAGUAUUUCUUUCUCCCUCUUUUCCUAGAAAUCUCCUCUGAUUUGCUUCUCUCUUUCCUUCUCCAAUCCGACACCUGGUCUCUACUCUGCCCCAAGGCCUUCAAGAUCCUUGUUCUCAUUGGCUGACUUUCCCCACCACCCCCUUAUAGCCCAAGCCAAGGACUUUGCUUGGUUGAAGGACACAUCUCACUCACUUCAUUCAUCCUUCAGGCCCCAGCAAGGAAGGUCACCCCUCUCCACCCCCACCCCCAGGAAUAGCCACAUCAUCUGCUUCAUGUGUCCCCACCCUAUCCUACCACAAAGCUUUGCACAAUAAACCACCAAGCUUUGAUGGCUCCAUUACUCAGCACUUAAUAUGCAGCUGGUAUUCUUUUCAUUCAUUCAAAAAAUAUUUAUUGAGCACCUACUAUGUGACAAGCCCUUGGAAUAUAUCCACGAAGAAAACAUUUGUACACACUGAUGUGCUGCAGGGUUUCCAUUUUUGUUCAUUAUCUGGGUAUGUGUCUCUGCUUUUCUCUUAAUACUGGAAGCUUGCCAAGAACAAGGGUGAGCUCUCCUAUACUCUCUGGCCCUGAACCCUGAGAGCAACCUGCAGGGCCCUGCAGAGGGCAUGGGGCAAGAUGAGUGUUUGUGUUUUUAUGUUAUGUACAAACACCAGCUACUGUGUGAUACUUAUUACUGAUGGCCGAUGGUGUACAGAAGGGAGUGCAAUGGGACAAACGCAUCCCUUCCUUUGGGAUCAGACACACAGGCUCUGGGUUCCAGUUCUGCUACUAACAUGCAACCUGAGCCUUAACCUCCCUAGACCUCAGUGUCCUCAUCUAUAAAACGAGAAUAAUAACACCAACCUCAGAGGGCAACUGUAAAAAUUAAAUGAGUUAAUGCAUGUUGGACUCUUAAAAUAGUAUCUAGUGUGGUAUAAGAUGAACAUCAAAAGAUUUUAUUAUUAAGUUUGGAAGAAUAGUCAUAAAAUAGCUUUCUACAUGAAACAUCUACUACUGACAUAACUUUAAAAAAAAUAGCCACAUACCCCAGAAAAACUCUUGCAUAAAUGCACCAGAAGACAUGAGAAAGGAUGUUCAUAGCAGCUCUGUUCAAUCUACAGAACUCUGGAAACAACCUUGUGGCUAUCGAGGUAGAAAGGCAAAUAAACUGUGGUAUAGCCAUGCAAUGAGUGCAAUCCACAGUGAAAAUGAACACAGGACAGCUACAGGAAGCAACAUUUAAUGAAAGAAACCAGAUGCACAAGGAUCCAUGCAACAUGAGUCCAUUUAUGUGAAGUUCAAAAGCUGGAAAAAGAAACAAUAUGUCAUUGCAAGAUGGGUGCAUUGGUUCUAAAACUGUAAGAAAAGCAAAGGAAUAAUUAAACACAAAAUGCAAGAGAGGAGUCACCCUAGGCCAGGAAGGAGUAGGGUACAAUCAGAACAAGGUACAUAGGAAGCUCCUGAAAUACACACAUGUUCUAUUUUUUCCUAUAAGUGGUAGGUAUUGCUACAGAUCUAACCACCUAUGCAUUUUUUGUGUUGAAAUAUUUCACAAUAAAAAUAAUUGUUAUCUCCACAAAGUUAAAAUCUAUCCUCUUUACCUUGCCAGAGCCAAGACCAUAGAGUGGAGAUUCUGCCAUCUUCCCUCCCCUCCUCCCUGCCACCUUCCCUCCCCUCCUCCCUUCCCCAUGACAAGGUUUUUUCACUCUGAAGAAAACAAGUUGAAUGUCCUUUUAGGUCUUCAAAAAUUAGCAGCAAUUAAUUCCUGAAGUUUAAUGAAAUGGUGUCACAUUUGAAUUUUUCAUAUUCUUACAUCUUUAAAAUUGCUUAGUAAGGACCAGCCAUUAGUAAUUAGCUUGUGUUUAUACAUGUUGUUUUUAUAAGGAGUUAUACUGGUAGAAAAGGUGAAGUGUGGAUGAGAUGUACUUUGACUCACAGUGCUCCUCAGGACACCCAACCGCUGGUUUACUGGGGACAUCACUGCUCAAUUGUGAGCAGUGCCCCAAAUUCCAGAUGAGGGUACAAAGAGCUUCAGAAGUGCUGGCCCAGCAGCCCUGAACUCACAAAGGGACAGCAGGUGCCAUACUCUUCUCUGGGGUGACCAGAUAGCUCAACACAGUCUGUGACCUCCCACAUUUGUCCUGCACAAGGCCACACUCUGAAUGUUUUGCACAGAUACCCUGAGAGCCCUAUUCUCUUCUAUUUUUUUCCUCUCCUCUCUUUUCCCAUCAAUCCUGCUUCUGUUCUCAUUCCCUAAGUCUACUCUGCCUGCCUUUGCCCUUGAAGCAUAGCAGCUCCAGGGGGCUAUAAGCCAGGCCAUUUCACUUCUCUUUUCUUCUCCUCAAUUUAAUGCAAACCUCUGUACUUUACGAGCUAAUUUUUCUAGGACCUGCUCUAUUGGAGUGGGGGGUGGUUCACUGGGUAAGUAGAACAUAGUACAGUCUAUCAAAGUAUUGCCAUAUACCAGAGGUAUGCAAAUAACUAAAACUGAUGUUUUCCACCCCGUCCUUCAAUUCUUAGCCACGGGGUGCUGCACAUCUAACUCAUACUCCUUCCCAGCCCCCAAGUAGCCUCACAUCGCCGUGUGUCCCUAAAUGACCCCUCAUGGUUCUAACCAUCCCAAUCCACUCUGACUCUGCCCGUCUUCCUUAGAUGGACUCUCUCACACCCUAAAUUCACAGAUACUCCCCUGUAAACAACUUUCACUACCCUCUUGAACUUAUCCAAAGAUUAGGAAGUCAAGGGGUUGUCACAGCUUAUAAGUGAGAAGGCAAUGCAACUCCUGGCUCCAUCACUUACCAGCUGGGAGACUUCGGGCAAGUUAUUUAACCUCCCUGACCCUUGGUUUCCUCAUCAGUAAAAUGGGGAUAAUGGCACAUACUUCAUAUGAUUGAUGUGAGAAUUAGAGAUCAUUUACGAUAUAUAAUGAUGAUCACAUAGUAGGUGACCAAUUAAAAAGAAACAUAUUCUUAUCAAACUAAGAUCCAUGUUUCUCUACACAGUUCUUUCUAAUUCUAAUUCUCUAUACAGUUUUUCCUAAUACAGGGGGAAAUGUACUGAAGUGAUCCAACCUCCAUCUCCUGGGUUCAAGCAAUUCUCCUGCCUUAGCCUCCCAUGUAGCUGGGAAUACAGGCACGUGCCACCAUAACGGGCUAAUUUUUGUAUUUGUAGUAGAGACGGGGUUUCACCAUCUCUGGUCUUAAACUCCUCCACUGAGGCUGGUCUUGAACUCCUGACCUCAGGUGAUCCACCCCCCUCAGACUCCCAAAGUGCUGGGAUUACAGGUAUGAGCCACUGCGCCCAGCUGUGAUUCAAUUUAGCAUCACCAAUCUGACAUUUUAUGCUUCCUGGGGUGAUAUAAUAAGAGUUACACAGCAUAUUUUAUGAAGUAUUCUGUCCCAACAAUGUUUAAUUUAAACCUAAUCCAGCCUCUAGCCCAGUGCUGUCCAACAGAAUUUUAUGUGAAAAUAAACAAUAAAUAAAAUAAAAAUAAAUAAUAAAGAAGUGUUCUUUAUAUGCACUGUCUAAUAAGGUAGGCACUACUUACAGGUAGCUGCUGAGGACUCAAAAUGUGGAUAGUGCAACUGAAUAACUAGAUUUUUAACUUAUUUAGUUUUUACUAACUUAAAUUUAAGUAGCCACAUCUGCCUAUUGUCUACCAAAUUGGACAUCCCAGCUCAAGAUUUACUUUCUAAUUUAUAGAAAAUACAAGGGCUAGAGCCACAAAUUAAAUUAUGUAAAAUGUAGUUUUAAAAUCCUUAGGACAGUUAGGAAAAUUGAAUCUGAGAUGAAUAGUAAGUGGUGCUUUGGAAUUAUUGUUAAUUUUCCUGAAUAAGAAAAUAGUACUCUCCUUAUUCUUAAGAAAUUCCUGCUGAUGUAUUUAAGGGUGACAUGCCAUGCUUUCUGCCACUCAAAUAAUUGGGCAACUGUGAAAGCAAAUAUGGUAUAAUGUUAACUGUUGAAUCGGGGUAAACAGGUGGAGCAUCAAUGCAUGUGUGUUGUAUUAUUCCAAUUUUCCUCAAUAUUUGAAAGCUUUCAUCAUAAAAAAGAUAAAAGACAAAUAUUUAAUAAUCUGCUGACUGUUCCCAUGGUAGGAAAAGUGAGAUGGUUUUCAGCUGCCAACUGAAAAAUCUGGAGAUGGGGAAAUCCAGAUUUGUGUUUCAGGAGCACUUUAGCCACAGCUGUGAUGGAAAUGAGAGAUGGUAUUUAUUAAUGCCUCAGCCUUUCCUGAAACCCCUCUCCCCACAUCACACUUAACACACAGGUCUCCUCCUCCCAGUUUCUCCCAGCACCUGGCCUCCCUUCUCUUCCCCUCGCCAGGCUCUACUCCUCCUUCUCGUCCUCUCCUCUGCCUUCCCCUUCCCUCCCCAAUGCCUGCAGAUGAAGGAAUGCCCUGCUGGCAAGACACUUUGAAGAUGAAACAUGCUGACUCCCCCAGAGCCCAAGACUGACAUCUUUUACAAAGAAGAGGGUGCAGGCCACUCCCCCAUUAAAGCACAUUCUGGAGAGGCGUUAGACCCGGCUAACCACCCAAGCCCAUAAAGCGCAAAUUGCCCCAACAUCAUCUUCACAGCCAAGCCCCUUCAGAAUCUGCGCAUAAAUAGGGCUGCGGUGCCCUGAGGAGCACAUUGGAGUUUCCAUCAGGACUCCAGGUCCCCUAUCCUGUCCUCUGCAACCCAAACGUCCAGGAGGAUCAUGACCUGCGGAUCAGGAUUUGGUGGGCGCGCCUUCAGCUGCAUCUCGGCCUGCGGGCCGCGGCCCGGCCGCUGCUGCAUCACCGCCGCCCCCUACCGUGGCAUCUCCUGCUACCGCGGCCUCACCGGGGGCUUCGGCAGCCACAGCGUGUGCGGAGGCUUUCGGGCCGGCUCCUGCGGACGCAGCUUCGGCUACCGCUCCGGGGGCGUGUGCGGGCCCAGUCCCCCAUGCAUCACCACCGUGUCGGUCAACGAGAGCCUCCUCACGCCCCUCAACCUGGAGAUCGACCCCAACGCGCAGUGCGUGAAGCAGGAGGAGAAGGAGCAGAUCAAGUCCCUCAACAGCAGGUUCGCGGCCUUCAUCGACAAGGUGCGCUUCCUGGAGCAGCAGAACAAACUGCUGGAGACAAAGCUGCAGUUCUACCAGAACCGCGAGUGUUGCCAGAGCAACCUGGAGCCCCUGUUUGAGGGCUACAUCGAGACUCUGCGGCGGGAGGCCGAGUGCGUGGAGGCCGACAGCGGGAGGCUGGCCUCAGAGCUUAACCACGUGCAGGAGGUGCUGGAGGGCUACAAGAAGAAGUAUGAGGAGGAGGUUUCUCUGAGAGCAACAGCUGAGAACGAGUUUGUGGCUCUGAAGAAGGAUGUGGACUGCGCCUACCUCCGCAAGUCAGACCUGGAGGCCAACGUGGAGGCCCUGAUCCAGGAGAUCGACUUCCUGAGGCGGCUGUAUGAGGAGGAGAUCCUCAUUCUCCAGUCGCACAUCUCAGACACCUCCGUGGUUGUCAAGCUGGACAACAGCCGGGACCUGAACAUGGACUGCAUCAUUGCCGAGAUUAAGGCACAGUAUGACGACAUUGUCACCCGCAGCCGGGCCGAGGCCGAGUCCUGGUACCGCAGCAAGUGUGAGGAGAUGAAGGCCACGGUGAUCAGGCACGGGGAGACCCUGCGCCGCACCAAGGAGGAGAUCAAUGAGCUGAACCGCAUGAUCCAAAGGCUGACGGCCGAGGUGGAGAAUGCCAAGUGCCAGAACUCCAAGCUGGAGGCCGCGGUGGCCCAGUCUGAGCAGCAGGGUGAGGCGGCCCUCAGUGAUGCCCGCUGCAAGCUGGCCGAGCUGGAGGGCGCCCUGCAGAAGGCCAAGCAGGACAUGGCCUGCCUGAUCAGGGAGUACCAGGAGGUGAUGAACUCCAAGCUGGGCCUGGACAUCGAGAUCGCCACCUACAGGCGCCUGCUGGAGGGCGAGGAGCAGAGGCUAUGUGAAGGCAUUGGGGCUGUGAAUGUCUGUGUCAGCAGCUCCCGGGGCGGGGUCGUGUGCGGGGACCUCUGCGUGUCAGGCUCCCGGCCAGUGACUGGCAGUGUCUGCAGCGCUCCGUGCAACGGGAACGUGGCGGUGAGCACCGGCCUGUGUGCGCCCUGCGGCCAAUUGAACACCACCUGCGGAGGGGGUUCCUGCGGCGUGGGCUCCUGUGGUAUCAGCUCCCUGGGUGUGGGGUCUUGCGGCAGCAGCUGCCGGAAAUGUUAGGCACCCCAACUCAAGUCCCAGGCCCCAGGCAUCUUUCCUGCCCUGCCUUGCUUGGCCCAUCCAGUCCAGGCGCCUGGAGCAAGUGCUCAGCUACUUCUCCUGCACUUUGAAAGACCCCUCCCACUCCUGGCCUCACAUUUCUCUGUGUGAUCCCCCACUUCUGGGCUCUGCCACCCCACAGUGGGAAAGGCCACCCUAGAAAGAAGUCCGCUGGCACCCAUAGGAAGGGGCCUCAGGAGCAGGAAGGGCCAGGACCAGAACCUUGCCCACGGCAACUGCCUUCCUGCCUCUCCCCUUCCUCCUCUGCUCUUGAUCUGUGUUUCAAUAAAUUAAUGUAGCCAA